AGGUCUCUGAAAUCUCGUGUGUAGGGAAGAAAAAUGAAUAUAUGCAUUUCUUUAAGCAAUAUUCUUAAUGCUUACUCAGAAAAAUGAAUUUGUUCCUAUGAUGACUGUAGGACUGCCGUCAGCUAAGCAAAGGCACUGAGUGUUUGGAAAUGAGGAAAUAAUAAAGUAAUGCGUAGACAUGGUGACAACAGUCCACAGGCUAAAAUAUUGGACCCAUAACAGACCCUUCCUGAACCCAAAGGAUGGAUUGUAGGAAUUCCCCAUGGAAAAUUACAAUCAAACAUCAACUGAUUUCAUCUUAUUGGGGCUGUUCCCACAAUCAAGAAUUGGCCUUUUCGUAUUCACCCUCAUUUUUCUCAUUUUCCUAAUGGCUCUAAUUGGAAAUCUAUCCAUGAUUCUUCUCAUCUUUUUGGACAUCCAUCUCCACACACCUAUGUAUUUCCUACUUAGUCAGCUCUCCCUCAUUGACCUAAAUUACAUCUCCACCAUUGUUCCAAAGAUGGUUUAUGAUUUUCUGUAUGGAAACAAGUCUAUCUCCUUCACUGGAUGUGGGAUUCAGAGUUUCUUCUUCUUGACUUUAGCAGUUGCAGAAGGGCUGCUCCUGACAUCAAUGGCCUAUGAUCGUUAUGUGGCCAUUUGCUUUCCUCUCCACUAUCCCAUCCGUAUAAGCAAAAGAGUGUGUGUGAUGAUGAUAACAGGAUCUUGGAUGAUAAGCUCUAUCAACUCUUGUGCUCACACAGUAUAUGCACUCUGUAUCCCAUAUUGCAAGUCCAGAGCCAUCAAUCAUUUUUUCUGUGAUGUUCCAGCUAUGUUGACGCUAGCCUGCACAGACACUUGGGUCUAUGAGAGCACAGUGUUUUUGAGCAGCACCAUCUUUCUUGUGCUUCCUUUCACUGGUAUUGCAUGUUCCUAUGGCCGGGUUCUCCUUGCUGUCUACCGCAUGCACUCUGCAGAAGGGAGGAAGAAGGCCUAUUCAACCUGUAGCACCCACCUCACUGUAGUGUCCUUCUACUAUGCACCCUUUGCUUAUACCUAUGUACGUCCAAGAUCCCUGCGAUCUCCAACAGAGGACAAGAUUCUGGCUGUUUUCUACACCAUCCUCACCCCAAUGCUCAACCCCAUCAUCUACAGCCUGAGAAACAAGGAGGUGAUGGGGGCCCUGACACAAGUGAUUCAGAAAAUCUUCUCAGUGAAAAUGUAGACAUACGUUCUGUGUUAGAGUCAAAGCGCUAGGUUCAUAUCAACUUAGUAGUGUACAGCAGUGAAGAAAAACAUUAUUACAUGCCCAGUGUGUCAAACAGAAGUUAAUCUAGAAGAAAUUUGUCUUUUAAUUUAGUCUUGACAAUAUUAUAAUACAUAUUAAUACAUAUUCUAAGACAUCUAUUUUGAUUUUGUUUGUGUGUGGUUUUUGUUUGUUUGUUUGUUUGUCUUUUUAAUGGAUUUUGGCUCUUGUUGCCCAGGCUCUAAUGCAAUGGCGCAAUCUCAGCUCCCCAUAACCUCUGCCUCCUGGGUUCAAGCGAUUCUCCUGCCUAGCCUCCUAAGUUAGCUGCGAUUACAGGUGUGAGCCACCAUGCCCUGCCUGUUUUUUUUUUAAUCAAAUAUAGGUCAUAUAUUUUCUACUAAAUUGUGGGCAACAGGGUUUCAUUAACAUGUAGAAAUCAAAACAAUAAAGGUCCAAACUAAUCAUAUCAUUCAGCAUAAUAAUUACAUAAUAGUUGUUUAUCUCCCAUUAUUAUAAAAAUAAGACAAAAAUAACAAAUUAGUUAAAAUUACUGAAUCUAAUUGAAUAUUAAAUAGUUUUUAUUUACUCUCAACUGGUAUGUAUGUCUUCUUCUUUUUCUUAAAGUAAUGUUUUACUAAUAAGUUUACCUGAGGAUAAAUAAUUAUGUUUGUGGAGCAGCCAAUUUGGCUUUAGAAAAACAAGAGUUUCUGUAUAAGAAGUUCUAUAGAAGUUACAGUCUAUAGACCCUCUUAGACUAUAGUUGACUUAGUGGAGUGUGGAGUAGGUUAUUUGAAUCAUUUCCCAGUCACGUCACAACACACUCAAGAUUUGCCUCCUCAGUUGCCACGGGUAUUUUCAUGCAAGACAUUCUCUUCUGCACAAUUUUAUUUCCACUUACUCUUCUCAUAAAUCAAUAGGACUAUUCAGCUUGGAUUGGGAUCAGCUCCUCUGCUCCACUAUUUUUAUACCUGCUUAGGCAUGUGCUUAAAAGGAUCAACAUUAUUUCAUAAAGGUUAUCUGCUUAGGUCCAUUCUCUGAGUGAAAGGCCAUUGCUCUCCAGAAGAGCCCAUUCCUGAGAGACUCUUUUAUCUCUGAGGAGAGAAGGCAAGAAGGAAGGUAGAAUGAGCAAGUAAGAAGAGCCUCAUAUUAUCCAAGUGACAGCAGUGGUGAAUGACUGAAUGGUCCUUGAGCAACACAGAUUUGAACUGUGCAGGUCCACAUAUAUGUGGAUUUUGUUCUGCCUCCACCACUCCUGAGACAACAAGUACAACCUCUCCUCCUCUUCCUCCGCCUCAGCCCACUCAACGUGAAGACAACAAUGAUGAAGAACUUUAUGACAAACCUCUAUCCCUAAAUAAAUAGUAAACAUAUUUUCUCUUUCUGAUGAUUUUCUCAAUAAGAUAUUCUUUUUUAGCUCACUUUACUGUAAGAGUAGAGUAUAUAAGACAUAUAAGAUACAAAGUUGUGUUAAUUGAAUGCUUAUGUUAUUUGUAAGGCUUGCUGUCAAUAGUAGGAUAUCAGUAGUUAGGUUUUGGGGAGUUCAAAGUUAAAUGCAUAUUCUACUGCUUGGCGGUCAGUGACCCUAAUUUCCGCGUUGUCCUAGAGUCAUCUGUACUACAAUUGGAAUAAUCAUUUUCAAACAAGAACAUUAACAUUUGAAUAGGAGAUACAAAUAUGGAUCUGGAUAUACUCAUUUCAAUUAAGCAUUUAGAGUUUACUAGAGUACUGAAUAAUUUAAAUUUUGACUUAUAGAAUGGCAAAUGUUUAUGACUUUCUUCUCCUCUAAUUUAAAUUAAGUAGAAUUUUCUCAUCAUUAGGACUGUAUGAGAAUGUCAUAAUAAUAUGAGAAAAGGUAGUAGUUGCCUGAUGUUGAAAGAUUUACCUAAUCUCACAUAAAUAACCAAAACAGCAUGGUACUGGUACCAAAACAGAAAUAUAGAUCAAUGCAACAGAACAGAGCCCUCAGAAAUAACGCCGCAUAUCUACAACUAUCUGAUCUUUGACAAACCUGAGAAAAACAAGCAAUGGGGAAAGGAUUCCCUAUUUAAUAAAUGGUGCUGGGAAAACUGGCUAGCCAUAUGUAAAAAGCUGAAACUGGAUCCCUUCCUUACACCUUAUACAAAAAUCAAUUCAAGAUGGAUUAAAGACUUAAACGUUAGACCUAAAACCAUAAAAACCCUAGAAGAAAACCUAGGCUUUACCAUUCAGGACAUAGGCAUGGGCAAGGACUUCAUGUCUAAAAUACCAAAAGCAAUGGCAACAAAAGCCAAAAUUGACAAUUGAGAUCUAAUUAAACUAAAGAGCUUCUGCACAGCAAAAGAAACUACCAUCAGAGUGAACAGGCAACCUACAGAAUGGGAGAAAAUUUUUGCAACCUACUCAUCUGACAAAGGGCUAAUAUCCAGAAUCUACAAUGAACUCAAACAAACUUACAAGAAAAAAACAAACAACCCCAUCAAAAAGUGGGUGAAGGACAUGAACAGACACUUCUCAAAAGAAGACAUUUAUGCAGCCAAAAAACACAUGAAAAAAUGCUCACCGUUACUGGCCGUCAGAGAAAUGCAAAUCAAAACCACAAUGAGAUACCAUCUCACACCAGUUAGAAUGGCAAUCAUUAAAACGUCAGGAAACAACAGGUGCUGGAGAGGAUGUGGAGAAAACACUUUUACACUGUUGUUGGGACUGUAAACUAGUUCAACCAUUGUGGAAGUCAGUGUGGCGAUUCCUCAGGGAUCUAGAACUAGAAAUACCAUUUGACCCAACCAUCCCAUUACUGGGUAUAUAACCAAAGGACUAUAAAUCAUGCUGCUAUAAAGACACAUGCACACCUAUGUUUAUUGCGGCACUAUUCACAAUAGCAAAGACUUGGAACCAACCCAAAUGUCCAACGAUGAUAGACUGGAUUAAGAAAAUGUGGCACAUAUACACCAUGGAAUACUAUGCAGCCAUAAAAGAUGAUGAGUUCAUGUCCUUUGUAGGGACAUGGAUGAAAUUGGAAAUCAUCAUUCUCACUAAACUAUCACAAGAACAAAAAACCAAACACCGCAUAUUCUCACUCAUAGGUGGGAAUUGAACAAU